ACACUUAUUAGCUGUGUGAUUUUGGACAAAUAACUUAGUUCUCUGAGUCUCAGUUUCCUCAUCAAUAAAGCUGAGAUCCUAUUCUACCUCCUAGAAUGGUUAAUGGGGAAUGAGACUGCAUGUGGAUGAAUCUAUAAAAUACUACAGAAGUUAGUUUUGGUUCUUUUACCAUAACAAUCCUGUGGGAUUGGCAUUUUAAAUUUCCAUUUUGCAGAUAAGCAAACCAACUCAGAGAGGUUAAUUAAUCUCAAAUAAUCAAAGACAGACUGUAUGCUGGAAUUGAAACCCAGUUCUGUUGAUUCCAAGUUUAGCACUACCAUGCAAGCCUACGUUUUUCCCAGGUGUUUUGGCACAGCCUGGGUGCUGACUUCUUUCUUCCCUUCAUACUCAGACCUGGAUACAGUCUUUAUCACUUCAAACAUGAUUGCUAAUUUUUGCUGUGAACCUGCUGAGUGGGUUCAGACAAAAAGCAUUCAUAUUUCAUGUCCAAAGGAAAAUGCAUCUUCUAAGUUUUUGGCACCAUAUACUACUUUUUCCAGAAUUCAUACAAAGAGUAUAACAUGCCUGGACAUUUCCAGCAGAGGAGGUCUUGGUGUGUCUUCUAGUACUGACGGGACCAUGAAAAUCUGGCAGGCUUCCAAUGGAGAACUCAGGAGAGUAUUGGAAGGACAUGUGUUUGAUGUGAAUUGUUGCAGGUUUUUCCCAUCAGGCCUUGUGGUCCUGAGUGGGGGAAUGGAUGCCCAGCUGAAGAUAUGGUCAGCUGAAGAUGCUAGCUGCGUGGUGACCUUCAAAGGUCACAAAGGAGGUAUCCUGGAUACAGCCAUCGUUGAUCGGGGGAGGAAUGUGGUGUCUGCUUCUCGAGAUGGGACAGCACGACUUUGGGAUUGUGGGCGCUCAGCCUGCUUGGGAGUCCUUGCAGAUUGUGGUUCUUCUAUCAAUGGAGUGGCGGUGGGUGCUGCUGACAACUCCAUAAACCUUGGCUCCCCUGAGCAGAUGCCCAGUGAACGGGAGGUUGGAACAGAGGCCAAAAUGCUGCUCUUGGCCCGGGAAGAUAAGAAACUUCAGUGCUUGGGACUACAGAGCAGGCAGCUGGUGUUCCUCUUUAUUGGCUCAGACGCUUUCAACUGCUGUACUUUUCUCUCUGGCUUCUUGCUAUUGGCUGGGACUCAAGAUGGAAACAUUUAUCAGCUGGAUGUGAGGAGUCCAAGGGCUCCGGUACAAGUCAUCCACAGAUCAGGAGCACCAGUUCUAUCCCUGCUAAGUGUCAGAGAUGGAUUCAUUGCUAGCCAAGGUGAUGGAAGCUGUUUUAUUGUCCAGCAAGACUUAGACUAUGUCACUGAGCUCACUGGGGCUGACUGUGACCCUGUGUACAAGGUAGCCACAUGGGAGAAGCAGAUCUACACAUGCUGUCGAGACGGUCUUGUACGACGCUACCAGCUUUCUGACCUCUGACUUCUUGGAAAGAGCAGUCCCGGUUAGUGAAAAGGUUUGACCCUGAUCAACAAUGAGCAGAAACAUCAUCAGUCCUUCCCAAGGACCAUGGCGUUUAAUGUCUUGGGCACCCCUUGGAAAUCACAGAAAGUCAGCUGUACUGGCCGUGUGGAACUCUCAUCCCAAGACCUACUUUGAACUGAGUAAGAAGGUCAUUGUGCCCACUGCAUUUGUUCCAACUUCUCCUUGUAUAAACUCACCCCAGCAACACAGGGCAAGGAUAUAGAUGCUUUUAGUUUGUUCUUAAACCAGUUUUGUUAAAUGUUUACAAGGACCUCAGUACUAAAGCCUGUUCUCUGGAGGAAAUAAAGAAAAUAUGUUUGGAGGUGCCUGAAUAUGAAGAACUUUGUUAAAUACUCUUACUCCAGCAAAAAGUUGGUCAGGACGAUGGAAUUCCUUCCUCAGCACUCCCUGUUGCCUGGCCAUAGAGAAGGCCUGCUUGGCAGUAGCAAUAAAUGUCCUGUAAGCUGCCACCUGGGAGAGAUUCUUAUGCAGGUGGUAACCAACUGUCCCAGUUUGCUUGGAACUAAGGGGUUUUCUGUGACUUGAAACUUUCAAUGCCAAAACUGGGGCAGUCUCAAACCAACAUGAUUGGUCAGCCUAUAUGUAGGUGAGGAAACUGAAUCAUAAGCAUUGUAAAGGCAUUGGCUGUCAAAGUGUGGUUCUUAGAACAGCAGCAUCAGUAUCACCUGGGAACUUGACAGGAAAUAGAAAUUGUUAGGCCCAAUCCUAGACCUAAAUCAGAAAUUCUACGGGUGCAGCCAGCAGUCUGUAUUUUAACAAGCAUUCCAGGUGAUUCUGAUGUAUGCUAAAGCUUGAGAGCCACUGAUCUAGAGGAAGAGAUGGUGGAGGGCACUUUAGUCACAGCUGGAACCCAGGGCUCAAAAUGACAAGAUCGGUCUGUAGGAGAUGAGGCCACAGAGGUUGGCAGAGCCCAAAUAGUGAAGGAGCACGAAUGUUAGCUAAGGAGCUCAGACUUUACGUGGUUGGCAGUGGGGAACCACUGAAGGGUUUUAAGCAAGAGAAUGGCAUGGUCACCUCCUUUUUUCUCUAAACAUAAAAAUGGAAUCAUAAUGUAUGUAUUCCAUGGCUUAUUUUCACUUAAUGUCUCUGAGAUUUUCCAUCUCAGUACAUGUAGACGUUCCUCAUUCUUUUUUAACAAUGUCCAGAAUAUGGAUACCAUAUUAUUUAUAUUUUUGAGAUUAUUAGAGAAAAGUUUCUUGAAAGAUGUAACACUUGAGCUGGGACAUGCAGAUUAAGAUUUUUAUUUAUUUAACGGAGGAAGGUCAUUUCUGGCUGGGGUAAUAAUGUUGUUGACAGAGUUCUUUUUUUUGUUUUUUUUGAGACGGAGUCUCGCUCUGUCACCCAGACUGGUGCGAUCUUGGCUCACUGCAACCUCCACCUCUCAGGUUCAAACGAUUCUCCUGCCUCAGCCUCCCUAGUAGCUGGGACUGCAGGCAUGCACCACCAUGCCCGGCUAAUAUUUUUUUUGUAUUUUUAUUAGAGAUGGGGUUUCACCAUGUUGGCCAGGCUGGUCUCGAACUCCUGACCUUGUGAUCCACCUGCCUUGGCCUCCCAAAGUGCUGGGAUUACAGGUGUGAGCCACCGUACCCGGCCGGCCACCAGAGUUUUUAAAGGCGUAUUCUCAUGUAAAUUUUUUUUUUUUAAAGACAGGGUCUUGCUCUGUUGCCCAGGCUGGAAUGCGUUGGCAUGAUUACAGCUUCUGCCUUAACCUCCUGGGCUCAAGCAAUCCUCCCACUUCAGCCUCCCAAGUAGCUGAAACCAUGGGUGCACACCACCACACUCGGCUAAUUUUUUAAAUUUUUUGUAGAGACAGAGUCUCACCAUGUUGCCCAGGCUGGUCUCAAACUCCUGAACUCAAGUAUUCCUCCCACCUUGGCCUCUCAUAGUGCUGGCAUUACAGGCAUGAGCCACGGCACUCAACCAGGAACUUUGUCUUAACUUUAAAUCCCAUUUUUUUCUACAACACCCUGUUACUUAAACCAAAGUGUAAAAAGAAAAUACUGCAAUUCAUUUAAUAUCUACUCUGUUCUAGAUACUAUAUUUAUAUAUCUAAUUCUUACAAGACUCAAAAAGCGAAUGUUAUUAUUUGUUUUAUUCCGAUAAGGAAACUGAGACUCAAUACAUUAAAUACCAGAGGCUUCAUUUGGACCUUGGACAGCACCUUCUGCUGCACUGUGUAAUCACAGGCAGGUAGCAAGAGACUUUUGUGACUAGAGCAAUUUCAUUUCAAGGUGCAGUUUGUGACAGGGUCAGGUAGACCAGAAUGGACAUAUUCCAGAACUUAGAAACAUUAAAUCCUAGGAGCUCCAGGUGGAACAUCUAAGAAGUCAGAUUAAGAAAACAGGAUGAGGCUGGGCAUGGUGGCUCACGCCUAUAAUCCCAGCACUUUGGGAGGCCAAGACGGGUGGAUCACCUGAGGUCAGGAGUUCGAGACCAGCCUGACCAACAUGGAGAAACCCCGUCUCUACUAAAAAUACAGAAUUAGCCGGGCAUGAUGGCGCAUGUCUGUAAUCCCAGCUACUUGGGAGGCUGAGGCAGGAGAAUCACUUGAUCCCGGGAGGCAGAGGUUGUGGUGGGCUGAGAUUGCGCCAUUGCGCUCCAGCCUGGGCAACAAGAGUGAAACUCCGUCUCAAAAAAAAAAAAAAAGAAAACAGGAUGAAAUGGGCCGGGCGCAGUGGCUCACGCCUGUAAUCCCAGCACUUUGGGAGGCCGAGGCGGGCGGAUCACAAGGUAAGGAGAUUGAGACCAUCCUGGCUAACACAGUGAAACCCUGUCUACAAAAAAUACAAAAAAAUUUAGCCAGGCAUGGUGGCAGGCACCUAUAGUCCCAGCUACUUGGGAGGCUGAGGCAGGAGAAUGGUGUGAACCUGGCAGGCAGAGCUUGCAGUAAGCUGAGAUCGGGCCACAGCACUCCAGCCUGGGCGACAGAGCGAGGCUCUAUCUCAAGAAAAAAAAAAAGAAAAAAAGAAAACAGGAAGAAAUGUUGUCAUUUAUUUGUAGAAUCUGAAACAUUUGAACUCAUAGAAGCAGUGAGUGGAAGAACCAGCGUGGUGGCUCACGCCUGUAAUCCCAGCACUUUGGGAGGCUGGGGUGGGUGGAUCGCUGGAGCCCAGGAAUUGGAGACCAGCCUGCACAACAUGAGGAAACUCUGUCUCUACUAAAAAUACAAAACUUAGCCAGGUGUGGUGGUGGGCACCUGUAAUACCAGCUACUAAGGAGACUGAGGCAGGAGAAUUGCUUGAACCCAGGAGGUGGAGGGUGUAGUGAGCUGAGAUUGCACCACUGCACUCCAGCUUGGGCAACAGAGCGAGACUCUCUCUCAAAAAAGAAAAAAAAAAUAUGUAUAUAUAUAUGUAUAUAUAUAUAUUUAUAUAUGUAGAAGCAGUGAGUAGAAUGGUGGUUACAGAGACUCGGGGAGGAGGAAUGGGGAAAUGAUGGUCAUAGGGUGCAAAGUCUCAGGAGGAAUAUAUUGUGUUUUGAGAUCUAUUGCAUAGCAUGGUAGAUUGCUAAGAGUAAAUUUCAAAUGUUCUCAACCCAAAAAAUGUUAAGCAUUUGAGGUGAUGGAUAUGUUAACUGGCUUCAUUUAAUUAUUCCAUAUUGUAUUUAUAAGUCACAAUAGGACUUUGUGGCCCAUAAUUAUAAACAAGUAUAAAUUGUCCAUUUACAAUUAAAAAUCAAUUAAAAGAAAA